GAGGCGGUGGGGCCCACAGCCAUGGCGGAGCCUGUGCAGGAGGAGCUCUCGGUCCUGGCCGCGAUUUUCUGCAGGCCCCACGAGUGGGAGGUGCUGAGCCGCUCAGGACCAGAAAAUAACACAGAGAAAAAUGAAAAUUGGUAAGGACUGACAUGGCUGGCUCAGUAGCUUUUCAAGACUUUCCCCCUGGACUACCAACAUGUUUCUUUCCUGUGGUUCCCUGCACCAGAGAGGACCCGAGACAGAUGGGACCGUGUUCAGAAUUCACACAAAAGCUGAAGGAUUUAUGGAUGUGGAUAUACCUCUGGAAUUGGUGUUCCAUUUGCCAGUCAAUUAUCCUUCAUGUCUACCUGGUAUCUCGAUUAACUCUGAACAGUUGACCAGGGCCCAGUGUGUGACUGUGAAAGAGAAUUUACUUGAGCAAGCAGAGAGCCUUUUGUCGGAGCCUAUGGUUCAUGAGCUGGUUCUCUGGAUUCAGCAGAAUCUCAGGCAUAUCCUCAGCCAACCAGAAACUGGCAGUGGCAGUGAAAAGUGUACUUUUUCAACAAGCACGACCAUGGAUGAUGGAUUGUGGAUAACUCUUUUGCAUUUAGAUCACAUGAGAGCAAAGACUAAAUAUGUCAAAAUUGUGGAGAAGUGGGCUUCAGAUUUAAGGCUGACAGGAAGACUGAUGUUCAUGGGUAAAAUAAUACUGAUUUUACUACAGGGAGACAGAAACAACCUCAAGGAGUACUUGAUUCUUCAGAAAACCUCCAAAGUAGAUGUGGACUCAAGUGGAAAGAAAUGCAAAGAGAAAAUGAUUAGUGUACUGUUUGAAACAAAAGUACAGACAGAACACAAAAGGUUUCUGGCAUUUGAAGUCAAAGAGUAUUCAGCGUUGGAUGAAUUACAAAAGGAAUUUGAAACUGCAGGACUUAAGAAGCUUUUCUCCGAAUUUGUACUUGCUCUGGUAAAAUGAAAUGGAAGACAGGAAUCUUUUAGUAAAAUAGCAGUGUUUUUUGUUGUUUUUGCAUUGGAUUUGGGGAGUGGUUAAUUGAAAUAGUCAAUUUUAAAGUUUCUCUGAAGCAAAAUGAUAGGCAUCAUUCUAACUUCAGGAACAAAAGCCAGUUCUGUUUUAUGAAAUAUUAAACAUGAAGAAAACUUGUAUAUUCUAAUGUUUGCCAGGAAAGGCUAGGUUCAGUAGAUGAGACAUUAUUUAAAAGAUAAAUUUAAAAAGAUGGUAAAUGAACACUUGUUUUUAUAGACAAUAUUUGUUUGAAACUAUGUAAUUUUCUGGCUAAUUUUCUUGUAAUUAAAUGAUUUUUUAAAAAAGA